ACUGGCACCCCACGCCUGUCCUAGAAGGUUCUUUCUGCCUGUUUUCUCCCCCCCCGCCCGGCUGUGGGGCCCAGCCACUGCACUUCACCGGAUGCCGUCUGGUUGGUCCUCAGGACUGAUACAGACCAGGACCCCAGGGCCAGCCCGUGCCAGGCUCCUAUGCUUCCAGGAGCACGGGUGGGUGGUCCUGCUGCCUGGCCGGCCAUCCUCCUGGGGUCGGUCUCUGGCCGAUCCUCCCUCCUCCUCUCAAGCCCUGCACAGCCCGGCCAGGCAGGUGCAUCUUGUUUGGCUGCUGAGGAGCCGGGGGUUCAGGGAAAUUAAGGAACGUGCCCAGGGACCCGGGGCCAGCCCGUGGGGACGCUGGGAUUGGAGCCCAAGCCCCAGGUUCGCCGCGCGGCUCUCGACUUCCUCUCCUUUCCCCCAGGGGCGAGCUCAGCGACCGCAGAGAGGUGGGGUCGAUCUCCCUGCGACCCCAGGGGGCCCGCGAGGCCAGUGCGCGGGCAGGAGCGGGGACGUGCUCAGAAGAGCCGGGCGCCGCCGCGCCCGCCCGCCCCCCGUCCCCCGGCUCCCGGCUCCGCGCGCCCCCCGCCGCCCCCGGGGCCCUGCUACCCCCGACCCGUCCCCUCCCGCCGGCCGCCCCCAUGGCCCGGCUGGGCGCGCUGCUCCUGGCCGCCGCCCUGGGUGCACUGCUCAGCUUCGCGCUCCUGGCCGCCGCGGUCGCCAGCGACUACUGGUACAUCCUGGAGGUGGCGGACGCCGGCAAUGGCAGCGCCUGGCCCGGGCGCGCAGAGCUGCUCUCCUCGCACUCGGGGCUCUGGCGCAUCUGCGAAGGGCAGAACGGCUGCAUCCCGCUGGUCGACCCUUUUGCCAGUGAGAGCCUGGACGUCUCCACCUCGGUGCAGCACCUCAUCUCACUGCUUCCACUGCCCCUGCGUUUCCAAGAGGACGUUUCCACGCAGACCUGUCCCAGUGCUGUGCUGCUGUCCCUAACCACAGUGCUGCACCGUGCAGUCAUUGUGGUCCUGCCCCUGAGCCUGGUCCUUCUCGUGUGUGGCUGGAUCUGCGGCCUGCUCAGCUCCCUGGCCCAGAGCGUGUCUCUGCUGCUUUUCACCGGCUGCUACUUCCUGCUGGGGACACAGGCUGAGACUGUAACCGGUAACCACCCAUCCACUGACGCGGCUCCAGCUCUGACUACAUGCCGAGUGCUGGCCAAGUGCUCCUCCGAAGGCUCCUCCGAGGGCCCCCCAGUCCCAGCUGCAGGCCACAUGAGAACAACAGUGAAGUCAAGGUCUCCUCUAGACAAUGAAAUCAGGAAGAAUCCAAAUGACCUGACCCUGCGGCCCAUCUGUGUCCUGACACUGGCGGGGGUCAGCAUCUACAUCAGCUACUCGCACCUGGCCUUUGCGGAGACGGUGCAGCAGUAUGGCCCGCAGCACAUGCAGGGCGUCCGCGUCAGCUUCGGCUGGUCCAUGGCCCUGGCCUGGGGCUCCUGUGCCUUGGAGGCAUUCAGCGGAACCCUCCUGCUCUCAGCUGCCUGGACCCUCAGCCUGAGCCCCCCAAUCUGUGGUCAUCUGAGUCCCCAGCAGGUGGGAGGGAGAGGGGGAGACUGAGGCCCAGAGCGGCAGAGGGACCCACCCAGAUCGCCUGGCGCCAGAGAGAUGCCGUCUCAGGCCAAGGCCUCCCUGGCCUCUGUUCUGUCCACUCUCCCCGAAGGGCAGGCUUGGUGGAGAAGAGGCUGAUGAGAGGGCCCGAGAGCCCCUCCGAUUUGCAGGGGUGGGGGGCAAGGAGCUGAGCGAUCCAGAUGUACCCCUCUGCCCCCUCCCUUGUUCUCAAGCCUGCUAGGUACUUUUCACUGAGCACUUCCGGGAAGAGCAGGCACCCAGAUCUCUGUCCUUGUCCUGGCACAGGCUGCUGCUGCUUCCGGCCCCCGACCCUUCCUCUCUGCAGCAACCCGGGGGAGGUAUGCCACUGUGAGUGCCCUGGUGGGCACACUGAGCUGGCAGAGAUGGAAGUCCCAGAAGGGUGGGGUGGGGGUGUCAUGCCAUGGUGGAGGAGUUUGGGGCCACUCCUUGCCUGCCUCAAAGGGGGCCUGGCUGAGGGUGCUUCUUGACCACAGGGGCCAGGGCUGCCUAGGGUGGCGCAGGGCUGGGCCUGGAGUUUGGGAUGCAGGCUUGUUAAACACAGGGCAGAACCCCAGGUUGGGAGGGGCUCAGUUUGCAGGCCCAGGCCCGCAGGCCCACUGCUGGUCCCAGGGUGAGACAGGUGAGAAGAGGGAUGGCCAGCACACACUUGAGUCCCCUUGGGCCACAAAGGCUGGGGCACGCCCACCGUUAUGCAGAUGGACAGUUGAGGUGGCUGCAGGAGAAGGGUUCCCAGGGCCUGUACAACACGUGGAAGCACUAAACGGCCCCGUUUGGGGUUUGGGGGCCCUUCCCGAGUCUUGAGAGGUCUUGAGAGGUGUGCUGGGGAAGGUGGCAGCCUCUUGUAGCUUGAUCUUCCUCCACCCUGCCCCACCCCUAGGUCUCUUUAUUGAUUCAAAGGUUAAGGAAGCUCCUGGGGGCUUGAGGGGGUGGCACAGUUUUGGUGGGGCCCAGUGAGGACAAAUCUGGGGGGUGAGCAGGGCCUCCUCUUCCUCCUGGUGUUUGAACGUUUACCAUUCCAUGUGGGACCAUUGUGCCAAUUUGUCCUUAAGUAAAUCACUUGUGCUGUGUGCAGUAUAAGCCUUUUAUUUUUCUUAGAACUUUUCAAAAUAGGUAACACAUGCCUGUCUGUCAUAAACAGUACAAACGUGAGCAAACACUGUCA